CUCUUCUUCUUAAACAAACCACAAACGGAUGUGAGGGAAGGAAGGUGUUUCUUUUACUCCUGAGCCCAGACACCUCACUCUGUUCCGUCUAAGCUUGUUUUGCUGAACACUUUUUUUUAAAAAAGGAAAAAGAAAAGGAGUUGCUUGAUGUGAGAGUGAAAUGGACGUAAGAUUUUAUCCACCUCCAGCCCAGCCCGCCGCUGCGCCCGACGCUCCCUGUCUGGGACCUUCUCCCUGCCUGGACCCCUACUAUUGCAACAAGUUUGACGGUGAGAACAUGUAUAUGAGCAUGACAGAGCCGAGCCAGGACUAUGUGCCAGCCAGCCAGUCCUACCCUGGUCCAAGCCUGGAAAGUGAAGACUUCAACAUUCCACCAAUUACUCCUCCUUCCCUCCCAGACCACUCGCUGGUGCACCUGAAUGAAGUUGAGUCUGGUUACCAUUCUCUGUGUCACCCCAUGAACCAUAAUGGCCUGCUACCAUUUCAUCCACAAAACAUGGACCUCCCUGAAAUCACAGUCUCCAAUAUGCUGGGCCAGGAUGGAACACUGCUUUCUAAUUCCAUUUCUGUGAUGCCAGAUAUACGAAACCCAGAAGGAACUCAGUACAGUUCCCAUCCUCAGAUGGCAGCCAUGAGACCAAGGGGCCAGCCUGCAGACAUCAGGCAGCAGCCAGGAAUGAUGCCACAUGGCCAGCUGACUACCAUUAACCAGUCACAGCUAAGUGCUCAACUUGGUUUGAAUAUGGGAGGAAGCAAUGUUCCCCACAACUCACCAUCUCCACCUGGAAGCAAGUCUGCAACUCCUUCACCAUCCAGUUCAGUGCAUGAAGAUGAAGGCGAUGAUACCUCUAAGAUCAAUGGUGGAGAGAAGCGGCCUGCCUCUGAUAUGGGGAAAAAACCAAAAACUCCCAAAAAGAAGAAGAAGAAGGAUCCCAAUGAGCCCCAGAAGCCUGUGUCUGCCUAUGCGUUAUUCUUUCGUGAUACUCAGGCCGCCAUCAAGGGCCAAAAUCCAAACGCUACCUUUGGCGAAGUCUCUAAAAUUGUGGCUUCAAUGUGGGACGGUUUAGGAGAAGAGCAAAAACAGGUCUAUAAAAAGAAAACCGAGGCUGCGAAGAAGGAGUACCUGAAGCAACUCGCAGCAUACAGAGCCAGCCUUGUAUCCAAGAGCUACAGUGAACCUGUUGACGUGAAGACAUCUCAACCUCCUCAGCUGAUCAAUUCGAAGCCGUCGGUGUUCCAUGGGCCCAGCCAGGCCCACUCGGCCCUGUACCUAAGUUCCCACUAUCACCAACAACCGGGAAUGAAUCCUCACCUAACUGCCAUGCAUCCUAGUCUCCCCAGGAACAUAGCCCCCAAGCCGAAUAACCAAAUGCCAGUGACUGUCUCUAUAGCAAACAUGGCUGUGUCCCCUCCUCCUCCCCUCCAGAUCAGCCCGCCUCUUCACCAGCAUCUCAACAUGCAGCAGCACCAGCCGCUCACCAUGCAGCAGCCCCUUGGGAACCAGCUCCCCAUGCAGGUCCAGUCUGCCUUACACUCACCCACCAUGCAGCAAGGAUUUACUCUUCAACCCGACUAUCAGACUAUUAUCAAUCCUACAUCUACAGCUGCACAAGUUGUCACCCAGGCAAUGGAGUAUGUGCGUUCGGGGUGCAGAAAUCCUCCCCCACAACCGGUGGACUGGAAUAACGACUACUGCAGUAGUGGGGGCAUGCAGAGGGACAAAGCACUGUACCUUACUUGAGAAUCUGAACACCUCUUCUUUCCACUGAGGAAUUCAGGGAAGUGUUUUCACCAUGGAUUGCUUUGUACAGUCAAGGCAGUUCUCCAUUUUAUUAGAAAAUACAAGUUGCUAAGCACUUAGGACCAUUUGAGCUUGUGGGUCACCCACUCUGGAAGAAAUAGUCAUGCUUCUUUAUUAUUUUUUUAAUCCUUUAUGGACAUUGUUUUUCUUCUUCCCUGAAGGAAAUUUGGACCAUUCAGAUUUUAUGUUGGUUUUUUGCUGUGAAGUGCUGCGCUCUAGUAACUGCCUUAGCAACUGUAGAUGUCUCGGAUAAAAGUCCUGGAUUUUCCAUUGGUUUUCAUAAUGGGUGUUUAUAUGAAACUACUAAAGACUUUUUAAAUGGCUUGAUGUAGCAGUCAUAGCAAGUUUGUAAAUAGCAUCUAUGUUACACUCUCCUAGAGUAUAAAAUGUGAAUGUUUUUGUAGCUAAAUUGUAAUUGAAACUGGCUCAUUCCAGUUUAUUGAUUUCACAAUAGGGGUUAAAUUGGCAAACAUUCAUAUUUUUACUUCAUUUUUAAAACAACUGACUGAUAGUUCUAUAUUUUCAAAAUAUUUGAAAAUAAAAAGUAUUCCCAAGUGAUUUUAAUUUAAAAACAAAUUGGCUUUGUCUCAUUGAUCAGACAAAAAGAAACUAGUAUUAAGGGAAGCGCAAACACAUUUAUUUUGUACUGCAGAAAAAUUGCUUUUUUGUAUCACUUUUUGUGUAAUGGUUAGUAAAUGUCAUUUAAGUCCUUUUAUGUAUAAAACUGCCAAAUGCUUACCUGGUAUUUUAUUAGAUGCAGAAACAGAUUGGAAACAGCUAAAUUACAACUUUUACAUAUGGCUCUGUCUUAUUGUUUCUUCAUACUGUGUCUGUAUUUAAUCUUUUUUUAUGGAACCUGUUGCGCCUAUUUAUGAAAUAAUAAAUAUAGGUGUUUGUAAGUAAAUUUGUUAGUAUUUGAAAGAGGUUUCUUUGAUGUUUUAACUUUUGCUGGCAAAAAAAAAUUCACGCUUGGUGUGAAUACUUUAUUAUUUAGUUUUUACAGUAACAUGAAUAAAGCCAAACCUGCUUUUCAUUUAGCAGCAAAUUAAAGUAACCAGUCCUUAUUUCUGCAUUUCUUUGGUUGAUGCAAACAAAAAACUAUUAUAUUUAAGAACUUUAUUUCUUCAUACGACAUAACAGAAUUGCCCUCCAAGUCACACAAGCUCCAAGACUAAACAAACAGACAGGUCCUCUGUCUUAAAAAGGUUACUUCUUGGUUCUCAGCUGGUUCUAGUCAAUUCUGAACCACCACCCCCCGCCCCCCGCAAAAAAGUAAAAGUCAAACCAAACUUCCUCAAGCUGCAUGCUUUUCACAAAAUCCAGAAAGCAUUUAAGAAUUGAACUAGGGGCUGGAAGAAGUGAAAGGGAAGCAUCUAAAAAUGAAAGGUGAGUAACCAGAUAGCAAAAGAAAAGGGAAAGCCAUCCAAAUUUGAAAGCUGUUGAUAGAAAUUGAGAUUCUUGCUGUCUUUUGUGCCUCUACAAGCUACUACUCAUUCCAGAAUUCCUGGGUCUUCCAAGAGGAUUCUUAAGGUACCAGAGAUUUGCUAGGGAACCAAAAGUGCUUGAGAAUCUGCCUGAGGGCUUGCAUAGCUUUCACAUUAAAAAAAGAAAAAGCUAGCAGAUUUACUCCUUUUUAGGGGAUCAUAUCAAGAAAGUUAGUCUGGUUGGAAACCAAGAGAAUGGCUGAUGUCUCUUUCUUGGAAUAUGUGAAAUAAAUUUAGCAGUUUAACUAAAUACAAAUAUAUGCAUUGUGUAAUCCACUCAGAAUUAAACAGACAAAAGGUAUGCUUGCUUUGGAAUGAUUUUAGGCAUUGUACAACCUUGAAUCACUUGAGCAUGUAAUAACUAAUAAAUAAUGCAGAUCCAUGUGAUUAUUAAAAUGACUGUAGCUGAGAGCUCUAAUUUUCCUGUCUUGAAACUGUAUAAGAACUCAUGUGAUUAAGUUCACAGUUUAUUGUUUGUCUGUUUAGUAUUUUAGAAAUAUACCAGCACUACUAAUUAACUAAUGUCUUUUAUUUAUUAUAUUAUGAUAAAGUAAAAAUUUCACUUGCAUUAAGUCUAAACUGAGAAGGUAAUUACUGGGAGGAGAAUGAGCAGCUUUGACUUUGACAGGCGGUUUGUGCAGGAAAGCACAGUGCCGUGUUGUUUACAGCUUUUCUAGAGCAGCUGUGCGACCAGGGUAGAGAGUGUUGAAAUUCAAUACCAAAUACAGUAAAAACAAAUGUAAAUAAAAGAAAACACAUCAUCAAUAAAACUGUUAUUAUGCGUGACCGUA